CCACAUCUUGCGAGUCCUUCCGAACGAGUCUCCUUUCCUUGGGGCUCGCAACCACCCAAUGAUCGAUUCAGGAGAAAAGAAGCCUGGGCGGAGAGCAGAGGAGGCAGUGACCUUCAAGGAUGUGGCUGUGAUCUUCACUGAGGAGGAGCUGGGGCUGCUGGACCCUGCCCAGAGGAAGCUGUACCGAGAUGUGAUGCUUGAGAACUUCAGGAACCUGCUCUCAGUGGGGCAUCAACCAUUCCAUGGAGAUACUUUCCACUUCCUAAGGGAAGAAAAGUUUUGGGUGAUGGGGACAACAAGCCAAAGAGAAGGGAAUUUGGAGUUACCCAGGUUUUACCCUCAAGCAAAGAGACUCUCCUCAGGCAUGACACUUCAAGAUCCUAGAGAUUACCUCUCAGAUGCUGACGACAACGUCCUGACCUCUUUCAAGUUAGGUUAACUUCUUUGUAAGGAUGUAUAACAGACAAAUAUACAAACUGUUUAUUCGUUAUUGCUUCUCCUUAAAGUUCCUUUGGAUUCAUAUUUCACUACAUAUGUAGUAUUUUAGCUUUAUAACUUACCACACAAAAUUUUAGACUGACUAAAAAAUUCACUAGAAAUAGCAACAAGUGAAAUGUAUAUAUUAAUUUUUUAAAUAAGUAUUUUAUUUCUAUCCAGAAUUUUACAUAUGAGACAUGGUGUGGUUCUAAAUUGGUCUCAUGCAAACCAAAAACCAGGGUGCACUUGGAAAACAGAAAAAUGAACGUUCAUUAAAGUUAAAUCCCACAUCCUAAGUGUGAAGUCUUGAAAACACUGAACAAAGACUUCACUUGUCCACAUGUCUUAUUUGGUGUUUUUGUUCGUUUGUUUGUUUCUGUUUUUGUUUUGUUUUGUUUUGUUUUGAGACGGAGUCUCACUCUGUUGCCCAGGCUGGAGUGCAAUGGCCUGAUCUUGGCUCACUACAACCUCUGCCUCCUGGAUUUAAGCGAUUCUCCUGCCUCAGCCUCCUGAGUAGUUGGGAUUACAGGUGUGUGCCACCACACCCGGCUAAUUUUUGUGUUUUUAGUAGAGACAGGGCAUCACCAUGUUGGCCAGGAUGGUCUCAAACUCCUGACCUCACAGUCCACCCGCCUCGGCCUCCCAAAGUGCUGGGAUUACAGGUGUGAGCCACCGUGCCUGGCCUACUUGUCCACAUGUCUUAAUUCUGUGUCCUUAUAGGAGGCAAGAUCCAAACUGAGAUGGAGACUGUUCCAGAAGCAGGAACACAUGAAGAAUUUUCCUGCAAGCAAAUUUGGGAACAAAUUGCAAGUGACUUAACCAGGUCUCAAGAUACCACCAUAAGUAACUCUCAGUUAUUUGAACAAGAUGACAACCCCUCCCAGAUUAAAGCAAGACUAUCUACAGUUCACACAAGAGAAAAACCUUUCCAGGGUGAAAAUUGUAAACAGUUCUUCAGUGAUGUUUCCUUCUUUGAUCUUCCUCAGCAGUUAUAUUCAGGAGAGAAGUCUCAUACCUGUGAUGAGUGUGGAAAAAGCUUCUGUUACAUCUCAGCCCUUCAUAUUCAUCAGAGGGUCCACAUGGGAGUGAAAUGCUAUAAGUGUGAUGUGUGUGGUAAGGAAUUUAGUCAGAGCUCACGUCUGCAAACUCAUCAAAGAGUCCACACUGGAGAGAAACCAUUCAAAUGUGAGCAGUGUGGGAAAGGCUUCAGAUGUAGAUCAGCACUUAAAGUUCAUUGCAAAUUACACAUGAGAGAGAAACCUUAUAAUUGUGAGAAAUGUGGGAAGGCUUUCAUGCACAAUUUCCAGCUUCAGAAACAUCACAGAAUUCAUACUGGGGAGAAGCCAUUCAAAUGUGAAAUAUGUGGUAAGAGCUUCUGUCUUAGGUCAAGUCUUAAUAGGCAUUGCAUGGUCCACACAGCAGAGAAACUGUACAAAUCUGAAAAGUAUGGAAGAGGUUUCAUUGAUAGGCUAGAUUUGCAUAAGCAUCAGAUGAUUCAUAUGGGACAGAAACCAUAUAAUUGUAAAGAAUGUGGGAAGAGCUUCAAAUGGUCCUCAUAUCUUUUGGUCCAUCAACGAGUCCACACUGGAGAAAAGCCAUACAAAUGUGAGGAGUGUGGGAAGGGCUACAUUAGUAAGUCAGGUCUUGACUUCCACCAUAGAACCCACACGGGAGAGAGAUCUUAUAACUGUGAUAACUGCGGGAAGAGCUUUAGACAUGCUUCUAGUAUUUUGAAUCAUAAGAAACUCCACUGCCAAAGAAAGCCAUUGAAAUGUGAAGACUGUGGAAAGAGGCUUGUAUGCCGGUCAUACUGUAAAGACCAACAAAGAGACCACAGUGGAGAAAACCCAUCCAAAUGUGAGGACUGUGGGAAGCGCUACAAGAGGCGCUUGAAUCUGGAUAUAAUUUUAUCAUUAUUUUUAAAUGACAUAUAAGUUAUACAUAUUUAUGGAGUGUGAAAUUUGAUACAUGUAUAUAAUGUGUGCUGAUUAAAUCAGUUUAAUUUCACCUGAAA